AUCACGUGUUGUUUAAUGAUGCGGAUACGUUCUGAGAAAUGUGCGGUCAAGUGAUUCUGACAUUGUGUGAACAUCCAGAAAGGACUUCACGGGGAUAUGGGGGACAAUAUAACAUCCAUCACAGAGUUCCUCCUACUGGGAUUUCCCGUUGGCCCAAGGAUUCAGAUGCUCCUCUUUGGGCUCUUCUCCCUGUUCUACGUCUUCACCCUGCUGGGGAACGGGACCAUACUGGGGCUCAUCUCACUGGACUCCAGACUGCACGCCCCCAUGUACUUCUUCCUCUCACACCUGGCGGUCGUCGACAUCGCCUACGCCUGCAACACGGUGCCCCGGAUGCUGGUGAACCUCCUGCAUCCAGCCAAGCCCAUCUCCUUUGCGGGCCGCAUGAUGCAGACCUUUCUGUUUUCCACUUUUGCUGUCACAGAAUGUCUCCUCCUGGUGGUGAUGUCCUAUGAUCUGUACGUGGCCAUCUGCCACCCCCUCCGAUAUUUGGCCAUCAUGACCUGGAGAGUCUGCAUCACCCUCGCGGUGACUUCCUGGACCACUGGAGUCCUUUUAUCCUUGAUUCAUCUUGUGUUACUUCUACCUUUACCCUUCUGUAGGCCCCAGAAAAUUUAUCACUUUUUUUGUGAAAUCUUGGCUGUUCUCAAACUUGCCUGUGCAGAUACCCACAUCAAUGAGAACAUGGUCUUGGCCGGAGCAAUUUCUGGGCUGGUGGGACCCUUGUCCACAAUUGUAGUUUCAUAUAUGUGCAUCCUCUGUGCUAUCCUUCAGAUCCAAUCAAGGGAAGUUCAGAGGAAAGCCUUCUGCACCUGCUUCUCCCACCUCUGUGUGAUUGGACUCUUUUAUGGCACAGCCAUUAUCAUGUAUGUUGGACCCAGAUAUGGGAACCCCAAGGAGCAGAAGAAAUAUCUCCUGCUGUUUCACAGCCUCUUUAAUCCCAUGCUCAAUCCCCUUAUCUGUAGUCUUAGGAACUCAGAAGUGAAGAAUACUUUGAAGAGAGUGCUGGGAGUAGAAAGGGCUUUAUGAAAAGGAUUAUGGCAUUGUGACUGACAGUGACCUAGGAAGUUACAUCAUUGAGCGGUUCUUAACCCAUCUCUGCACUGGUGGGACCUCUGCCCUCAAUGGACAUGAGAAUUAUCUGAGACAUUUAUUUAAAAUGGAGCUAUCUCCUGCCCUACCUUUAAAUGACUGAUUUCAGCAGAUGUGGGAUGAAAUUCUAGAAAUUGAUCUCUUCAAGUUGUGCUGCAGCCACUCCACACCAGGACAAUACCCCUUACAAUAUCCUCAUUAGCUUUUGAUCCAGUCCCAUACCUCCCAUAAUGUUUUCCUCAAAACACUGGUCCCUUCAGAGGACUUUAAAAAUAAGUUCUAUAGUCAAAUAAGUUUGAGACUUACUUCACAUCAGAUGCCUCUGUCUAGGGAUCACAAUUCAUAUUAGCAUAGUGAAUGCUGUAAAUAUUUCUCUAGGAAAGAAUAAUUCUAUACCAGCUUUAAGCCAGUGUUUUCUAAACUUAUGUGAGCACAUAAAAUUUCCUUUGUAAUACUUAGUAACAGUUUCCUGGAACAGGAGAUCUUGAUAUUAAUUGACUCAUUGUGAAUACUUCCUACAGCCCCCUUCUAGGGCAGAAUGAUUUCUUUUUUCCUUGCAAAGUGAGCCUCUAAAGAGAUGUAGUUCUGAGCAUUAUGCCUCGAUCAGUCUGUAAAAAUCCGGGUUCUGUUUGGAUACAGACCGUGAGGGACCCUGUCUCUACUGUUCAAUGGUAGAUCAUCUAAAGAAAAUAAAUGCAAUCCUGUCCUUCAUCAUGGAUCGGCAUUCCUGCUAUAGAAGCUUCAGGAGAUGACCUCAUUCAACCUCACAAUCUUCUAAAUUUGAGAUUUUUAAGAAAUAUGAUUCAGUAUACAUCUGCCUGUGUUUGCCGCUGAAUGAAAUCAAUCUAAUUUUUCUAAUUCAGGGUUUUCAAGAUAAACCCAGAUUUCUCAAGAAAGAAAAAUCUAGAAAGAUUUCAAAAUCCACCACCUACACACUUAAAAGUUGUAGCAGCUUCUUAUGCCAUGGGAA